AACAUGCAAGAUGGCGGCCCAUCACCGGCAGAACACAGCAGGGCGGAGGAAAGUGCAGGUUUCCUAUGUUAUUCGAGAUGAAGUGGAGAAGUACAACCGAAAUGGAGUCAAUGCUCUGCAGCUGGAUCCAGCACUAAAUAGACUUUUCACAGCCGGUCGAGACUCUAUCAUAAGAAUAUGGAGUGUCAAUCAGCACAAGCAAGAUCCAUAUAUAGCAUCUAUGGAACACCAUACUGAUUGGGUAAACGACAUUGUACUCUGUUGUAAUGGGAAAACAUUAAUAUCUGCUUCUUCUGACACGACAGUAAAAGUAUGGAAUGCACACAAGGGAUUUUGCAUGUCAACAUUAAGGACACAUAAGGAUUACGUAAAGGCCUUAGCAUAUGCCAAGGAUAAAGAACUAGUAGCAUCAGCUGGGUUGGACAGACAAAUAUUCCUUUGGGAUGUGAAUACUCUAACAGCAUUGACUGCCUCAAAUAACACUGUCACAACUUCUUCUUUAAGUGGAAACAAAGAUUCCAUUUAUAGCCUGGCCAUGAAUCAACUGGGAACAAUCAUUGUAUCAGGGUCCACUGAAAAGGUGUUACGGGUAUGGGAUCCAAGAACAUGUGCAAAACUAAUGAAGCUUAAAGGGCACACGGAUAAUGUGAAGGCAUUGCUAUUAAACAGAGAUGGCACGCAAUGCCUGUCAGGCAGUUCUGAUGGGACAAUUCGCCUUUGGUCCCUUGGCCAGCAGAGAUGUAUAGCAACAUACCGAGUCCAUGAUGAAGGUGUUUGGGCGCUGCAAGUCAAUGAUGCCUUCACACAUGUGUAUUCUGGUGGAAGGGACAGGAAGAUUUAUUGUACAGACCUAAGAAACCCUGACAUUCGGGUGCUAAUUUGUGAAGAAAAAGCACCAGUUCUCAAGAUGGAGCUUGAUAGAUCAGCUGAUCCUCCUCCUGCAAUUUGGGUUGCAACAACUAAGUCUACAGUAAAUAAAUGGACUUUGAAAGGAAUUCAUAAUUUUAGAGCCUCUGGAGAUUAUGACAAUGACUGUACAAAUCCUAUAACACCUCUUUGUACACAACCUGACCAGGUUAUUAAAGGGGGUGCUAGUAUUAUUCAGUGCCACAUUCUUAAUGAUAAGAGACAUAUAUUAACCAAAGAUACCAAUAAUAAUGUGGCAUAUUGGGAUGUAUUGAAGGCAUGUAAAGUUGAAGAUCUGGGCAAAGUGGAUUUUGAAGAUGAAAUUAAGAAAAGAUUUAAAAUGGUGUAUGUGCCAAAUUGGUUCUCAGUAGACUUAAAAACAGGGAUGUUAACUAUUACUUUGGAUGAAAGUGAUUGUUUUGCUGCCUGGGUUUCUGCAAAAGAUGCUGGUUUCAGCAGCCCUGAUGGGUCAGAUCCAAAAUUGAAUUUAGGAGGACUUUUACUCCAAGCACUCCUGGAAUAUUGGCCUAGAACACAUGUGAAUCCAAUGGAUGAAGAGGAAAAUGAAGUAAACCAUGUAAAUGGGGAGCAGGAGAACCGAGUGCAGAAGGGAAAUGGAUAUUUUCAAGUGCCCCCACAUACACCCGUGAUCUUUGGUGAAGCUGGAGGUCGCACACUGUUCAGGCUGCUCUGCCGAGAUUCCGGGGGUGAGACUGAGUCUAUGCUUCUUAAUGAAACAGUGCCACAAUGGGUAAUUGACAUCACUGUGGAUAAAAAUAUGCCCAAAUUCAACAAAAUUCCUUUCUACCUCCAACCUCAUGCAUCUUCAGGAGCAAAAACCUUAAAAAAAGAUAGACUCUCUGCUAGUGACAUGCUCCAAGUCCGAAAAGUUAUGGAACAUGUUUAUGAAAAAAUUAUCAACUUGGAUAAUGAGUCUCAAACCACUAGCUCUUCUAAUAAUGAAAAACCAGGAGAACAGGAAAAAGAAGAAGAUAUUGCUGUGUUGGCAGAGGAGAAAAUUGAACUUUUGUGCCAGGACCAGGUAAGUGGACUUGAGGACUACAGCCCCAAUUUUUCCAGUGCUGGUGCUCAUAAAGAGUUACAUGCCUUUGGGUGGGGGGCUUCUACUUUUAGAGGGGCUCUAAGGAGCCCUGGGCCUCUCCUACCUAAAGCCCACCCUAAAGCUCCUCUUUACUGCUGGGGAGAUUUUCAGAGAAGGGAUACAUAGACAAAUGUGGAUGUGCUGGUAGCUUUUUUUUCUGACAAGAAAAAAGACACAUGGUCUUCUUGAUUUGCAAAAAGCAUGUGCCAUGUUUAUGAUUUAGAGUGAAGGUGUGCGGAGAAAUGGCAGAACUGUUUUUUAAAUCAAGAUGCACUCAAAACGUAUCCUCAGAGGAAUGGCUGAAAGAUGGCCUGGUGUUUCUGGCAUAGUCACAAAAGAUGUACAUCUCACUAAGCUCAAUUUCAUUCCCGCAUGCAUGGAAGCCGUGACAGCAAGAAUUGGAUACCAGGCAUAGGGGAGGAGUGAGCAAGCUGGAUCACCUGAUGAGAGUCCCUGAGUUAAUGAUAAGGUUUUAGAUAUUAGAGACUUUGAAAUUUUUAAAUUUAAUUUUGGCUAUUCAGGUUUUGGAUCCAAAUAUGGACCUUCGAACAGUGAAACACUUCAUAUGGAAGAGCGGUGGAGACCUCACCCUCCAUUACCGUCAGAAGUCCACGUGAAGGCUGGGCUAAUGCUCCUGGAUAUUCAUUUACGACCUUCCUCUAUGGCCCCAAGAGUAGUCCUAGGAAGCCCACUGAUCCCCAACGGGAGCAAGACUUCUAACGGCUGAUUGGUAUGGACCGAGAUUAUCUUUCAAUUGAAGUGACUAAUCGAGAUGUAAUAUAGAAACCAGUCUCCAUGUGUAGAUUAAGCUGUCCCCAGGGAAGCAGAGUGCAAGAGCAGAAGAGCCCCAAGCAGACUAUGUCUUUCAAGAUGUACAGAAGACUGACAACAGGCCAGUGCAGACUUUGCUUCCUCCUUUUGUUUCAAAGGACCUUAUCUACCCAUUAACACUUGUUAGAGACACCUCAGUCGGGCCACAACUGUCUCUGUUUCAACUUUAAGCCCACACACUCUGUAGCUUUUCUAAAACAGUACAUUCCAUUCAUGCAGUAGAUAUGAAGGCUUUUUCCAAGUUUGUCAUAUAAAGUAAUCAAAUUGUUUUCACCGUUUAAGACAGUUAUUUUUAAUGGGAAUUUGCUGUUGCACAAUUUGAGAACCAGCCCAUUUCAUAAUAAAAGAUUAAUGUUGGGCUUGUUGUUAAUAUUGCAUCUCAGAUGUGUUCUUGUAGGAAGAUCUGUUGAAAUUCCAGGUGCUGGAUCAUAGCACUUGGACUGUUGGGCCGGAGUUUGUGCAGCCCAUGCCUAGCGAUGCUGCACCUCCCAUGAUGUCCUGGCUUUGUGGCAACCCCAGGGAGGUGCAGCAGUUUCACUCCUUCCUCCACUGUGUCCAGUUUUAUUUACACAAAGCGAGCUGAGACCACAGGUUCUUGCUCUGGAUGAGCAGCAUGACACCAUCAAAAUUUAAGACCAUGAUGAAAUUUCAGUUUCAUUCAAAUGUUACCUAAAAUUUAUGGUGUCAGAAUAAAGGGAGAUCAUAGUGAGUUAAUUUGAUAUUCAUAUCCUGGAAGUAUACAUAUUUGUUUUUCCAAAGUUUUAUAUGCAGGUUUUUGUUGUACCUGUAUCCAGAUCUUCUUUUCACUGUUCUAACAAUCUAACACUUUCAUAGAAUCAUUUGGAUCUUGUAUAGAGUGUAACUUAUUGGGGAUAAACACUUCAACUUUUGGCAGAAAAUACUUUGGAUUCUCCCCAAGGUCAUUUGUAUUCAGAGUAAAUCAGUGGUCCACCCCCAUAAAACUGUAAGACAAGCCUCCUGUAUGAAGCCAGAAGCACAAGUGCCUUCAGAGGGCAGUUGAUUCCAGUCCAGUUGCCUCCCUAGCUUGUGUGUGGCCUGCCUCCACCAUAGCAGGGACUAGGGAGGGAGGCAGGGAACGUUUUUUCUUUUCUACAUCUUCACAGGUUCGGCUGGGGGCAGCUGAUAGGCCUAAGGCCAUACCUUACUAUUUAAGAUACUCUGAUCGCACAACUGCAGAGACAGGGUUCCCUCACUGCUAGUCAGCUUCUUUUGGAAACUGGACAGGCCAUUGCCACCUGCACUUUGAAGAAGUGAGCAAAGACGUGGCCACAUUUCUAAUAAGUUGAAAUGGUCUUUCUCCCUUCCUCAGAGAGCAACCAGCUUCUUUUUUUUUAAAAGUCCUUUCUAUCUGUUGGAUACAACAGUGUGCUUUUGGUGCACAUUUUUUAGCAAUAGUUGUGAAUUAAUGGCAAAGAAAAAAAAAAUUAUUUACCAGCCCUCAGUUGUGUUUGCCCGAGGGGCCUUUGAGCAAAGAAAUGGGUUUUGCUGGGUCAUUUUGCCCUGUGUGCUAAGCCUUGGGUGGCUGCAUUCCCCUCCUGUCAUAGAUCUGACCCCCAGCAUGAUUGUAUUUCUUUCCCCUCCAGUCAAACCGUAAUACAGUUUCCAGAAAAUUCGACAGUCUGCAAUGCCAAAAGGGUAAAAAUCUGUAUUUCACAGUUGUAUAGAAUAAAGGCUUUAGUUAAAAUA